AUUCCAAAUUCGGGAACCACCAGAAAGGCUGGCCUCUCUUCAACAUGGGAUCUUCUGGACUUUUGAGCCUCCUGGUGCUAUUCGUCCUCUUAGCGAAUGUCCAGGGACCUGGUCUGACUGAUUGGUUAUUUCCCAGGAGAUGUCCCAAAAUCAGAGAAGAAUGUGAAUUCCAAGAAAGGGAUGUGUGUACAAAGGACAGACAAUGCCAGGACAACAAGAAGUGUUGUGUCUUCAGCUGCGGAAAAAAAUGUUUAGAUCUCAAACAAGUCUCUCUGCAGAUGUAUGCGAAAUGCCAAAAGAAACUGGCCCCUGCCUGGCUUAUUUUCUUCAUUGGUGGUAUGACAAGAAAGAUAAUACUUGCUCCAUGUUUGUCUAUGGUGGCUGCCAGGGAAACAAUAACAACUUCCAAUCCAAAGCCAACUGCCUGAACACCUGCAAGAAUAAACGCUUUCCCUGAUUGGAUAAGGAUGCACUGGAAGAACUGCCAGAAUGUGGCUCAUGCUCUGAGUACUGUUCCUGUACCUGACGGAUGCUCCAGACUGGCUUCCAGUUUCACUCUCAGCAUUCCAAGAUCUUAGCCCUUCCCAGAACAGAACGCUUGCAUCUACCUCCUCUUCCUCCAUCUUUGGCUCUUUUGAUGCACAAUAUCCAUCCGUUUUGAUUUCAUCUUUAUGUCCCCUUUAUCUCCAACUUCUAGAACUCCCAGUUUAUACCUGUGUCACUCUCAAUUUUUUCCAGUAAAGUACUUGAUGUAGUCCUGUGCCUUGAGGCUGAGUGAUUGACAUCUUUUUGGCACAUUACACUUUGCAGAGUAAGGGAUCAUUGAGGCUUCUGGUGACAUCAUUCAAGGGAGUGAAGACAAUCAGAACUUUGAGAGUUCAGAGUUCCAGGAAUAUUGUUAUUGUUAUCUUCCUCUGUUUCUACAAAAGAUUGUAAAACCCUUUUUAGGCAAGGGCCCAAGGACAGUGCCUUAGUUUGGAUCCUCUAGAAACUAACCCUGGGAAAAGGGCAUGGGUGCAGGUAGUUUGUUUGAGAGAUUUCCCAGGACAUACAAGAUGGGGAGUGAGAUGAGUAAUUCAGGGAAGAGAAGGGAAGAGAGAAGAGUCUAUUAUGAGCUGGUUACUACUGUGGCUCAAUCCUAUUGGGGACCUUUUAAAGAAUCAUGUAAAACAGGCUUACAAAUUUUCUUUUUAAAAAUAUUUUAUUUUAUUUUACGUUCCGGGAUACAUGUGCAGGACCUGCAGGUUUGUUACAUAGGUAAGCCUGUGCCAUGGUGGUUUGCUGCACCUAUCAACCCAUUACCUGGGUAUUAAGCCCCGCAUGCAUUAGCUAUUUAUCCUGAUGCUUUCCCUCCCCCUGCCCCCUCAACAGUCCACGUGUUCUCAUUGUUCAUCUCCCACUUGCAAGUGAGAACAUGUGGUAUUUACUUUUGUUCCUGCGUUACUUUGCUGAGGAUAACGGCUUCCAGCUUCAUCCAUGUCCCUGCAAAGGACGUGAUCUCAUUUCUUUUUAUGGCUGCAUAGUAUUCCAUGGCAUAUAUGUACCACAUUUUCUUUAUCCAGCCUAUCGUUGAUGGAUAUUUGGUUUGAUUCCAUGUUUUUGCUAUUGUAAAUAGUGCUGCAGUGAACAUACACAUGCAUGUAUCUUUAUAAAAGAAUGAUUUAUAUUCCUUUGAGUGUAUACCCAGUAAUGGGAUUGCUGGGUCAAAUGGUAUUUCUGGUUCUAGAUCUUUCAGGAAUUGGCACACUCUCUUCCACAAUGGUUGAACCAAUUUACAUUCCCAACAGUGUAAAAGCAUUCAUGUUUCUCCACAGCUUUACCAGCAUCUGUUGUUUCUGGACUUUUUAAUAAUCACCAUUCUGACUGGCAUGAGAUGGUAUCUCAUUGUGGUUUUGAUUUGCAUUUCUCUGAUGAUCACUGGUGUUGAGCUUUUUUUCAUAUGUUUGUUGGCCGCAUAAAUGUCUUCUUUUGAGAA